ACCACUGUCCUCAGCCAAACUGCAGGGACUCCUAAGUAGAUCAGAGCUCCUGGAACUUUCUCAUCUUUUCAGCAUCUCAACCCUGUGGAAUCUUUUAACUCCCAAGUGCUACCAGGAUAUUUGCGAUGUACUCUGGAAUCCCUCUGGAAGGAGCUGUCCUCACAGAAUGAAGGAUUAGAGGAGUUAAUAAAUAAGCAAACCCAACCUUUCUCCUGGGGAAUUGUGAUCCUCUCUAGAAGCUAGGCUGUGGACCUGAAUUUGCAGGAGAAGCCAGGAGUCAUCUGUGAUGCUCUGCUGAUAGCAUAGAACAGCCCUGGCAGGGCCAGGACUACUGCACUUGCACUGCCCUUACUUUGAAGCAGAAGCUGGUGAACAUGGGGGGCUACACUGGGGAGGUGUGUGUCAGGGCCAAGGUCCUCUGCCUGAGUCCUGAGAGCAGCGCAGAGGCUUUGGAGGCUGCAGUGUCUCCGAUGGAUUACCCUGCGUCCUAUAGUUUUGCAGGCACCCAGCACAUUGGAAGCCCUGCUGCAGUCCCUCGUGAUUGUCUUGCUCGGCUUCAGGUCUCUCUUGAGUGACCUGUGCAGCUAUGAGGUUUUAAAUCUGCUCACAGCCCAGCAGUAUGAGAUAUUCUCCAGAAGCUUCCACAAGAACAGAGAAUUGUUUGUCCAUGGCUUACCUGGCUUAGGAAAGACCAUCAUGGCCAUGAAGAUCAUGGAGAAGAUCAGGAAUGUGUUUCACUGUGAGGCACACAGAAUUCUCUACAUUUGUGAAAGUCAGUUUCUGAGGAAUUUCAUCAGCCUCCCAAAGUGCUGGGAUUACAGGCGUGAGUCACCGCGCCCGUCGUUGGAUUCGCAGACACACCGUUUCCAAAGGCGCAGAGUCGAUAACAGCGCGUGCGGUGCCACCACUUCCGGGGAGUCGAGUGCCCGAUAGAAAUGCAGCUGAGCGAGGGGCUAGCCGCACACGGACGCGGAGAGCAGGAAAGUGGAAAAGAACUCAGGUCCCCCUACUUGGUGAAGAGUGCGCAGACAUGGACCUCGCCAGAAAAGAAUUUCUGCGUGGAAAUGGCUUAGCUGCUGGGAAAAUGAACAUCAGUAUUGAUUUAGACACAAACUAUGCUGAGCUGGUUCUAAAUGUGGGAAGAGUCACUCUUGGAGAGAACAAUAGAAAAAAAAUGAAGGAUUGUCAACUGAGAAAACAGCAGAAUGAAAAUGUCUCACGAGCUGUGUGUGCUCUGCUGAAUUCUGGAGGGGGAGUGAUCAAGGCUGAAGUUGAGAAUAAAGGCUAUAGUUAUAAAAAAGAUGGAAUAGGGCUAGAUUUGGAAAAUUCUUUUAGUAACAUGCUGCCAUUUGUUCCUAAUUUCCUGGACUUCAUGCAGAAUGGUAACUACUUUCACAUUUUUGUGAAAUCAUGGAGCUUGGAAACCUCUGGUCCGCAGAUUGCCACGUUGAGCUCCAGUUUGUACAAGAGAGAUGUAACGUCUGCAAAAGUCAUGAAUGCUUCUGCUGCACUGGAGUUCCUCAAAGACAUGGAAAAAACUGGAGGGAGAGCAUAUUUAAGACCAGAAUUCCCUGCAAAAAGGGCCUGUGUUGAUGUACAAGAAGAAAGUAACAUGGAAGCCUUGGCUGCUGAUUUUUUUAACAGAACAGAACUUGGUUAUAAAGAAAAAUUGACCUUUACUGAAUCCACACACGUUGAAAUAAAAAACUUCUCGACUGAAAAGUUGUUACAACGAAUUACAGAGAUUCUCCCUCAAUAUGUUUCUGCAUUUGCAAAUACUGAUGGAGGAUAUUUAUUCGUUGGUCUAAAUGAAGAUAAAGAAGUAAUUGGCUUUAAAGCAGAGAAGAGUUAUCUUACUAAGUUAGAAGAAGUAACAAAAAAUUCCAUUGGGAAACUGCCUGUGCAUCACUUCUGUGUGGAGAAGGGGACGAUAAAUUACUUAUGCAAAUUCCUUGGAGUAUAUGAUAAAGGAAGGCUUUGUGGAUAUGUGUAUGCACUCAGAGUGGAACGCUUCUGCUGUGCAGUGUUUGCUAAAAAGCCUGAUUCCUGGCACGUGAAAGAUAACAGAGUUAAGCAGUUGACCGAGAAGGAAUGGAUCCAGUUCAUGGUGGAUUCAGAACCAGUAUGUGAGGAACUGCCCUCUCCAGCAAGUACAUCAUCACCUGUCUCCCAGAGUUAUCCUCUUCGUGAAUAUAUUAACUUCAAAAUUCAGCCACUGAGAUAUCACCUUCCAGGGCUAUCAGAAAAGAUAACUUGUGCUCCAAAAACCUUCUGCAGAAAUCUGUUCUCACAACAUGAAGGACUUAAGCAAUUAAUAUGUGAAGAAAUGGGCUCUGUCAAUAAGGGCUCACUGAUCUUCUCUAGGAGCUGGUCUUUGGAUCUGGGCUUGCAAGAGAACCACAAAGUCCUCUGUGAUGCUCUUCUGAUUUCCCAGGACAAGCCUCCAGUCCUAUACACCUUCCACAUGGUACAGGAUGAGGAGUUUAAAGACUAUUCUACACAAACUGCCCAAACUUUAAAACAGAAGCUGGCAAAAAUUGGUGGUUACACUAAAAAAGUGUGUGUCAUGACAAAGAUCUUCUACUUGAGCCCUGAAGGCAAGACAAGCUGCCAGUAUGAUUUAAACUCGCAAGUAAUUUACCCUGAAUCCUACUAUUGGACAACAGCUCAAACAAUGAAAGACUUGGAAAAGGCCCUUUCAAAUAUCUUACCUAAGGAGAAUCAAAUCUUUUUGUUUGUUUGUUUGUUUCGUUUUUGUUUGUUUGUUUGUUGGUUUGUUUGUUUUUUCUUGAGAUGAGUCUCACUCUGUCACCCAGACUGGAGUGUAGUGACACGAUCUCGACUCACUGCAACCUCUGCCUCCUGGGUUCAAGCAAUUCCCUGCCUCAGCCUCCCGAGUAGCUGGGAUUACAUGUGCCUGCCACCACACCUGGCUAAUUUUUUUUUUUUUGUAUUUUUAGCAGAGAUGGGGUUUCACCGUCUUGGCCAGGCUGGUCUUGAACUCCUGACCUCGUGAUUCAACCCCCCCCCCCGGUCUCCCAAAGUGCUAGGAGUACAGAUGUGAGCCACCGCGCCCGGCUGGAGAAUCAAUUCUUUUAUAGACCAAUUAGCCUUUGACAUUUCCAGCAUCUCCCAGAUAAUCAGUAUAGAUAAGGAUGUUUAAAUCUUGUCCAAGGCUCACUUGAAUCAUGGAAGAUGGACUGGGCUACAGAGAUAUUUUUCAUUAUAUAUUUGGUAACAUUCUCUAAUUCUCUAAAAAUACGUCUUUGAAAACAUUGCAAGUUAGGCAACUUGACGUGAUGUUGGAAAACUGGGAUUAGCCUAUGUUCGCUUCUUCCUAAGUUCUUUAUAGAUAUUCCUUAAGGGAAAUUAGAAAAAUUAAUUACCUACACAUGUUUUGCCAUACCAAGAUGUCAUUUGACUAUAAAGGAAAUAUCAGACAUUCUUAUCCAAUGGACAUGGAAAACAUAGUUCUCUAAUAUCUUCUUGAAAACUAUAUUGCAAUGAAAUGCAGCCAAUGAAGAGAUGAAUCAAAAUGGAGAACUUGCCGAGUUGGAUGGAUCACUUGAGGUCAGGAGUUGAAGACCAGCCUGGGCAACAUGGUGAAACCCAGUCUCUACUAAAAAUAUAAAAAUUAGCCAAGUGUGGUGGCACACACAUGUAGUCCCAGCUACUCGGGAGGCUGAGGCAUGAGAAUUGCUUGAACGCAGGAAGUGGAGGUUACAGUGAGCCAAGACCACACCACUGCACUCCAGCUUGGGCAAGAGAGCAAGACUCUGUCAUCUCUAUGCAAAUAAACUAGAAAAUCUAGAAGAAAUGGAUAAAUUCCUGAACACAUGCAACCUCCCAAGACUGAGCCAGGGAGAAGUCAAAUCCCUGAACAGGUCAAUAACAAGUUCUGAAAUUGAGGCAGUAAUUACUAACCAAAAAAAGCCCAGGACCAGACAGAUUCACAGCUGAAUUCUACCAGAGGUACAAAGAGGAGCUGGUACCAUUUCUACUGAAACUAUUCCAAACAAUAAAAGAGGAAAGAAUCCUGCCUAACUCAUUUUAUGAAGCCAGUAUCAUCCUGAUACCAAAACCUGGUAGGGACACAAUAAAAAAAGGAAAACUUCAGGCCAAUAUCCCUGAUGAACAUCAUUGCAAAAAUCAUCAAUAAAAUACUGGCAAACCGAAUCCAGUGGCAUGUCAGAAAAGCUUAUCCACCACGAUCAAGUGGGCCUCAUCCCUGGGAUGCAAGGCUGAUUCAACAAACACAAAUCAAUAAAUGUAAUUCAUCACAUAAACAGAAACAAUGACAAAAACCAUAUGAUUAUCUCAAUAGAUGCAGAAAAAGACUCUGACAAAAUUCAACAUCCCUUUAUGUUAAAAACUCUCAAUAAACUGGGUAUUGAUGAAACAUAUCUCAAAACAAUAAGAGCUAUUCAUGACAAACCCACAGCCAAUAUCAUACUGAAUGGGCAAAACCUGGAAGCAUUCCCUUUGAAAAUUGGCACAAGACAAGAAUGCCCUCUCUCACCACUCCUAUUCAACAUAGUAUUGGAAGUUCCGGCCAGGGCAAUCAGGCAAGAGAAAGAAAUAAAGGUAUUCGAAUAGGAAGAGAGGAAGUCAAAUUGUCUUUAUUUGUAGAUGAGAUGAUUUUAUAUCUAGAAAAUCCCAUCAUCUCAGCCUCCAAAUUCCUUAAGCUGAUAAGCAACUUCAGCAAAGUCUCAGGAUACAAAAUCAAUGUGCAAAAGUCACAAGCAUUCCAUUACACCAACAAUAGACAAGCAGAGAGCCAAAUCAUGAGUGAACUCACAUUCACAAUCGCUAAAAAGAGAAUAAAAUACCUAGAAAUACAGCUAACAAGGGAUGUGAAGGACCUCUUCAAGGAGAACUACAAACCACUGCUCAAGGAAACAAGAGAAGACACAAACAAAUGGAAAAACAUUCCAUCCUCAUAAACAGGAAGAAUCAAUAUCAUGAAAAUGGCCAUAUUGCCCAAAGUAAUUUAUAGAUUCAAUGUUAUUCCCAUCAAACUACCAUUGACAUUCUUCACAGAAUUUCAUAUGGAAUCAAAUCAGAAUUAAAUGAAAUUAAAUUUCAUAUGGAAUCAAAGAAGACCUUGUAUAGCUAAGAUAAUCCUAAACAAAAAGAACAAAGCUGGAGGCAUUAUGCUACCUGACUUCAAACUACACUACAUGGCUACAGUAACCAAAACAGCAUGGUACUGGCAUAAAAAGAGACAUAUAGACCAAUGGAACAGAACAGAGACCUCAGAAAUAACACCACACAUCUAUAACCAUCUGAUCUUCUACAAACUUGACAAAAACAAGCAAUGGGGAAAGGAUCUUCUAUUCAAUAAAUGGUGCUGGGAGAACUGGCUAGCCAUAUGCAGAAAACUGAAACUGGAUCCCUUCCUUACACCUUAUACAAAAAUUAACCCAAGAUGGACUAAAGACUCAAACUGAAAACUGAAACUGGAUCCCUUCCUUACACUUUAUACAAAAAUUAACUCAAGAUAGAUUAAAGACUUAAAUGCAAAACUCAAAACCAUAAAAACUCUAGAAGAAAACCUAGGCAAUACCAUUCAGGACAUAGGCAUGGGCAAAGACUUCAUGACAAAAACACCAAAAGCAAUUGCAACGAAAGCCAAAGUUGACAAACGGGAUCUAAUUAAACUAAAGAGCUUCUGUACAGGGAAAGAAACCACCAUCAGAGUGAACGGACAACCUACAGAAUGGGAGAAAAUUUUUGCAAUCUACCCAUCUGACAAAGGUCUAAUACCCAGAAUGUACAAGGAACUUAAACAAAUUUACAAGGAAAAAACAACCCCAUUGAAAAGUGGAUAAAGGAUAUGAAUAGACAUUUCUCAAAAGAAGACAUUUAUACAGCCAACAAACGUAUGAAAAAAAACUCAACAUCACUUAUCAUUAGAGAAAUGCAAAUCAAAACCACAAUGAGACACCAUCUCACACAAGUCAAAUGGUGAUUAUUGAAAAGUCAAGAUAAAAGAUUAUUUAAAACUUUUAAAUAAUCUUUUAUUAAAAGAAUAUUUAAAACUUUUAAAUAAUCUUUUAUUAAAAGAAAGAUUAUUAAAAAGUCUCCACUGCACGGCGAGGCUGUGGAGAAAUAGGAAUGCUUUUACACUGUUGGUGGGAAUGUAAAUUAGUUCAACCAUUGUGGAAGACAGUGUGGCGAUUCCUCAAGGAUCUAGAACCAGAAAUACCAUUUGACCCAGGAAUCCCAUUACUGGGUAUAUACCCAAAGGAAUGUAAAUCAUUCUACUAUAAAGAUACAUGCAGGCGUGGCGCGGUGGCUCAUGCCUGUAAUCCCAGCACUUUGGGAGGCUGAGGCGGGUGGAUCACCUGAGGCCAGGAGUUUGAGACCAGCCUGGCCAACAUGGUGAAACCCCAUUUCUACUAAAAAUACAAGAAUUAGCUGGGAGUGGUGGUAGGCGUCUGUAAUCCCAGCUACUUGGGAGGCUGAGACAUGAAAAUUGCUUGAACCCGGGAGGCAGAGGUUGCAGUGAGCCAAGAUCACCCCAUUGCACUCCAGCCUGGGUGACAAGAGCAAAACUCUGUCUCAGAAAAAAAAAAAAAAAGACACAUGCACACAUAUGUUUAUUGCCCCACUAUUUACAAUAGCAAAGGCAUGGAACCAACCCAAAUGCCCAUCAGUGAUAGACUGGAUAAAGAAAAUGUGGUACAUAUACACCAUGGAAUACUGUGCAGCCAUAAAAAGGAAUGAGAUCAUGACCUUUGCAGGGACAUGGAUGAAGCUGGAAGCCAUCAUCCUCAGCAAACUAACAUGGGAACAGAAAAUGAAACACUACAUGUUCUCACUCAUAAGUGGGAGCUGAACAAUGAGAACACAUGGACACAGGGAAAGGAUUAACACACACCAGGGCCUGUUGUGGGGUGGGGAGAGUGAGGGGAGGGAACUCAGAGGAUGGGUCAAUAGGUGCAGCAAACCACCAUGGCACAUGUAUACCUAUGUAACAAACCUGCACAUUCUGCACGUGUAUCCCAGAGCUUAAAGUAUAAUAAAAAUUAAAAAAAAAAAAAAGAACUUAAAACAGUGGGAGCAUGUUCACACUCUUGGAGUCUUUCCAGCCCUGAACCUCAGGCAGCCUGUAUCAGCUGCUGGUGAUGGGUGACCUGGGCAUGGGGAAGACCACCAUCAUCAAACAGUGAGUGCACCAGAACUCCUCCUGGCUGGCACCCUGAAGCCACCACUGUGUGAACUGUGCAUUCAAGGUGCUACACUGGGACCCAGAGGCCUUGGCACACCUACAGCUGUGGAACAUUGCAAUGAGGAAAGAUUGGGAAAAUGACAAGAGCCUGUUAUCUGGAACUUACAGGCGCAUUUAUUGUCUCCAGUAUCACCAGGCCAGCCCCAUUUGAAGCAGAGCUAAAGUGGAAAAAUGAUUUGGACUAAACGUUAACACAUGGCAGACCAAUUUCUAUGGUUCUGUUGGCCAAGAAAUGUGACCAUGGGAGGAUGAACGCAGGAACAAUAGCCUCAAGAUGGGCCAGAUCUACAUGGAACAUAGUUUUGCAGUAGGAAAAUAUAAACUUUGGUGAAACCUUCAGAUGCCUGAUAAAAUAUUAUAUGAAAAUGUACUCUUGAAGUUUUGAUUUAUGGAGGUGACUGAGUGUCAACACAGAUGGACUAGCGCCAUUGAAAAAAGACUUUAUUACUUAUAGUUCCAAGAGAAGGGGACUUGCUCUGUCAUGCAGGGUCAUGUGGUAAAGCAUCCAGUUGGUUAAGGAAAGAGGAGCAGAAGUGAGGGGAAAAUCUAAUUCGGAACCUUUAUUAUUAGGGUUUCUGUGGGAAAGGUCCAGCUGGGCAGGGGGAACAGCUUAGGACUCAAUAGUUUGAAUAAUUCUGAUGGGCUUUGGGGCCUAGGGACGGUCCCCAGUUGUCUGUUACAUGGCCCUGGGUUUAUGUAGGGUAGGGAAAAUAUUGGCUCGAUGUGUGAGUAGCUUAGAGUAUGAGCUCUGGGUCACAGCGGGGAUGUAAAGAAUGUUGGCCAUUAGUUUGGCCCUGUGAUUAAUGGAUGCCAAAUAGACAAGUACAGAACCUAGGAAAACACAGUAAGACCCAUUGCCCCUGGGCCUAUUUGGCAUCAUCGUAAGAAACCUGGGGUGGUAAUAGUGGACUUAUUUAAAGGAUGGGGUACAGUUGCCCUAAAUAGCCUAGAAAAUAUUUUAUUGUAAGAGUAAGAUAGAAGAACAAUGUGGAAGUAUAAAGAGCCCUUGUAGGCUGGUCCAUAACUAAGUUCUUCAUUUGCAUGUCAUUAGUCAAGAAAGUAGAUCUGAAAUUUUUGGAGGUUUUUACUAUUAUCUUGGUGGAGUUUUAAAGUGGGUUAAAAGUUUGAAAUACAUAUAUAUAUAUAUUAUAUAUAUAUUUAUAUAUAUAAUAUAUAUAUAUUUUAUAUAUAUAUAUUUUAUAUAAAACAGGUCCUGCAGUCAGGUUGUUGGGGGAUAGGAACUAAUACAUUAAUAAUGCAUGUGUAGACUAGCGUGUGUGUAUAACCAAGGAGGAGUGGUCAUGGUCAGAGACACAGGGCAGGAAGUCACGGGGGAAAGCUUGAGGGGGUAGUAGGGGUAGGCACUGGGGAGUUAGUGGUCCUCUUCCCAGUGGGUUGAGGGAUUGACUCAGGAGGCAACAGCCUUCAGAGAAAGGCAAUACUAUCCAUUAAUUUUUGUUAUCUUUUUAGACACAGGGUCUUGCCCUUGUCACCGAGGCUGGAGUGCAGUGGUGUGGUCAUAGCUCAUUACAGCCUUGACCUCCCGACAUCAAGAGAUUCUCCUGCCUCAGACUCUUGAGUAGCUGGGACUACAGGUGUACACCACCAUGCCCAGCUAACUUUUAUAUGUUUUGUAGAGAUGGGGUCUCCCCAUGUUGCCCAGGCUGGUUUGAACUCCUGGGAUUAAGCAGUCCUGCCUCAGCCUCCCAAAGUGCUGGAAUUAUAGGCAUGAGUCACUGUGCUUGGCCCUCCAUUAAUUCUUAGAAUGACGUAGGUAGUGGUAACUACUAUUAAAUUUUCCUUCAGGCAUAGGAGUGCGGGGUGUAUGUUUUGGCAGAGAGCAAGGAGUAUGCCAGGAUGAUAGGCUAAGCAGACAGCACACUCAGAAACACAAUAGAAUCCCUGAUAUCAAAGGAAAAAAGGCCAAAUGUUCGGUGUGCAGUUUGUGCCUGAGAAGAGGCAGUCCAUGGGUGUCACUGGGGUGAAGGUUUUUGUGUUUAGGGUGACGCCAUGUCUGGUGCAGGGGUAAAUUCAUCUCUGACGGUAAGCUGGAUCGAUGUCAUCUGAGGCAGCAUAAUCUCCAGCAGUGAGUGCCUAUCCAGGAAAAUGUCAUCUAGGAUAUGGGUCUUGAGUAUUUCUUUUAAGUAAAUACAGACUCAGGUUGAUGUGGGUCUUAGCAUUUGCCAUGAUUGAUUAAAACAAUGGCUUGUAUGGAGGGUUGGUGCCUCCAGAUGAUAAAACAACAAAAGCACCCAUACCAGCAGUAAGAUCAGCAGGCUGAGCAUGGCAGCUCAUGCCUGUAAUCCCAGCACUUUGAGAGGCCAAAGCAGGUGCAUUGCUUGAGCUCAGGCAUUCAAGACCAGCCUGGGCAACAUGGUAAAACCCUGUCUCUACAAAAAACAUAAAAAAUUAGCUGGGCGUGGUAGUGUGUGCCUGUGGUCGCAGCUUCUCAGGAGGCUGAGGUGAGAGGAUUGUCUGAACCCAGGAAGUAGAGUGGGGAGUGAAUCGUGAUCACGCCACUGCACUCCAGCCUGGGUAACAGAGUGAGACCUUGUCUCAGACCAAAACAAAAAGCAAAAACAAACAAACAAAACAAAAAAGAUAAACAGAAAACAGAAUGGUGUGCAGCUGCAUUUGACAGAGUUUUGGUUUUUGCUUGCUUGCUUGCUUGCUUCAUGGUUGAAGUUUAGGCUCAAACGGGUCCCAUAUCAGAUAAGCAGCUGCCUAGCCCAUUGGACAAUCACUAUUAAUUGGACCCCAGAGAAUAUACACACCUGCUGUGGCCUCCUGAUGGGGGGGGUUUGAUAUUGAAAAUCUAUAAAAAUAGGUUAAGGCCUGGGGCAAGAUAAAGACCCAUUGAGAGGUCCAUUUGUUGGACUGGAACUUUAAAAGAAGUUGUUUGGGGAGACUCUUAUGUCUCUCUGUUAAACUGGCUAUUUGGGACCUAUUAGGGUCAUGAAAGUUUUAUUGAAUGCCUGUUUGUUUCGGGAGCCCAUUCAGUGUGUAUUUUGCAAUGUGAAAUGUGUGCCUUGGUUAUUACCUUGGUAAUUGUAAGGCCUCAUAUGGUGGCCUUAAUAUACAUAGACACGUGAUUUUGGGUAUCUAAGAGGAAAGAGGUUCUUAGUGUUCCUUAAUCUGAAAGGGACAAUUCAUUAGGCAAUGGCUCAAUUGUUCAAAAGGAAUAUGGAGAUGGGGCCAUUUGUUGGCCAGGGCAUCCAGCAUUCGGUAAUAUUCCACCUAGCUCCAUCAUGUAUGGUGGUUGGCAGUGCCAUUCAUAUAGUCCGUGAACUUCUAUUGCUGUUCACUCAGUCAAUCCAAAGGAGCUUUCCAGGUAACCAAGGGGUCUGGAGGAGAGGUGACCUCCUCCAGCACUAUGGCAUCUGGCAAGGGACCAAGGACUGGGGACGUCACUCCCUUCUGCGUGUGAAUAUGCUAGAGAGCCCAGGACUUGGUAGCCUCCUUGAGACAGGUUAGAGACAAACCUGGGCCCUCUGAGAGGCUGAGCUUGCAGGGUGCUGUUUCCAUGACUGAAAGCAUAACAGGUAGCCAGGUAUGGAGGGUCACAGACUCAGAAUCUGUGAAAGCCUCUAUGUCCAGGAGAGCCCAGUAUGGAGCUAGUCAUUUGUGGUUUUAAUGGCAUAUAGCAUGAGGCUGAGAGCCCUCAGGCAAUUCGUAGCCAUCACAGGUGGUCUAGACUUUAGGAGGCAUGAGUAGAGCUUGUUAAAGUCUCUUCAGUAAAGGAAUCAAUGCAGGCACCAAUGGGUCUGUCUGUUGGUAUUAAUUUGGAUAGAUUUUAGAGCCUUUUUGUUUGAGGCUGCCACAUUUAAAGUGGGUUCAUUUGUGAGUUACAGCUCAAUGAGAUUAAGUAAAAUUUGUAAGUGAAGAAUAUUUUGCCAUGAAAACCCAAAAAGGAUGAAAAGAUGUUGGACUCUUAUGUCCAUAUGAGUAGAUUAAGUGACAUCUCCUUGGAGGAGGUUAUUAAUGUAAUAUCAUAUCUGUGCUCCCAGAGGAAGGUGCAUGCACUUAAGAUCUUGUCUGUCCCUGUCUCUUUAAAAAGAAGGCCAUCUGAAAAGGCUAUAUACUGUAUGAUUCCAACUAUAUGACAUUCUGUAAAAGGCAAGAUUAUGGAGACAGUAAAAUGAUCGGUGGUUUCCAAGGAUUAAGGGAGUGGGAGGAAUGAAUAGUUGAACCACAGAGGAUUCUUAAGGCCAUGAAAAUCCUGUGUUUGAUACUAUAUAGUAGAUAUAUGUCAUUAUACAUUUGUCUGAACCCAUAAAAUGUACAAGAAGAAUGAACGCUAAUGUAAAAGUCGCAAUGGAUUUUGAGUGAUUAUGAUGUAUUAAUUUAGAUUAAUCAAUUGUAACAAAUGUACCACACUAAUGGGAGAUGUUGCUAAUGGGGGAGGCUAUGCAUGAGUGCGGGCAGUGGGUAUAUGGAAAAUCUUUGUACUUUCCGCUCAAUUUUGCUGUGAAUCUGCUCUAGAAAAAUUAAGUAUUAAAAAAGAUCUUGUCUGUAAGAUGUGUGCAUGAUGGCAAAAUUGUGAAGGUACUGAGGUGUAGCCUGCAAGAGGUAUAUUGUGUCUCUUCAGCAAUGGAGGCAAACUACAGUGGAGUCUGUUGAAAUAGGCACGGAAUUGAACAUAUUGAACAUAUUAGCCAAGUCUGUAAGAACAGAGUAUUUAGCAGUUAUUGAUUGGAUAGAGUUAAUAAUGUUAAUCAUACUAGAUACUGGCUAUGAGGCCCUAGUCGACAAGACCACAGCAAUAAUGUUGUAGUCCUCCACCGUGAGGUGCCUGCUGCUUAUUAUUUUCCAGGUUUAAGAACAGGCAACACUGGGCUGUUAAACGGACAAGCAGCAGGGAAUACUUAUCUCCUUUAUCCCUUUUAUGUUAUAUAAAUGAGGUUUUAUGUAACAACUUUCAAUCCUUCAAGGGCCUAUUUUAACUUACAUUGAACCAUAUUAACUAUUUUAAUGGGAUUUAUAUAAUCCUAUUUUAUCAAGCCAAUUUUUGAGUGCCAAAAAUUUAAUUUUAAUUUAUUAUUUAUUGUGACAUGGAGUCUAUGUUCAAUACGAGAUACUUUAAGGCACUGAGUACAACAACUAUGAGCAAUUCAAUCAAGAUAUAAAAUAAGGCAUAGCUAUUUUUAAAAAGCUAUUUAGCUACCUUUUAAAAUUAUAUGGGGUACAAUGUUUAAAUUUGUUGGAACCUCAGGCAUAAGUAUAAUUUGAGUAUUUAUUAAGUCCACGAGGUUUCUCAAUUGGUGCAUUUUGGCAAAUGUUAAAGUUAAUUUAGAGCUUUCAGUUCUGGCCAGGCGUGGUGGCUCACGCCUGUAAUCCCAGCACUUUGGGAGGCCGAGACAGGCGGAUCACUUGAGGCCAGGAGUUCGAGACCAGCCUGGCGAACAUAUAGUGAAACCUCAUCUCUACUAAAAAAUACAAAAAUUAGCUGGAUGUGGUGGUGUGCUCCCGUAGUCCCAGCUACUUGGGAAGCUGAGGCAGGAGAAUCACUUGAACCUGGGAGGCGGGGGUUGCAGUGAGCCAAGAUGGCACCACCGCACUCCAGCCUGGGUGACAGAGCAAGACUUUAUCUCUCUCUAAAAAAAGCAAAAAACAGAAAACAAAAAACCUUACAGUUCUAAACCCAAUCACGACCUUAGCUAUCUUUUUGUUAUAUAAAUUCUUUGGUAUACAAAUUUUCGAUUUCCAAUUGGGUGAAAUUAUGGAUGUUUGUUUUAAUUUAGAUAUACGUUUGAUAUCUUUAUCUAUGUACAUGUACAAUCUAUUCAUUAUGUCUAUAUUAACCUAAAUGCUCAUCAAUGACAGAUUAGAUAAAGAAAAUGUGGUACAUAUACACCAUGGGCUACUACACAGCCAUAAAAAAGAACAAGAUCAUGUCUUUUGCAGGAACAUGGAUGGAACUGGAGGCCAUUACCCUUAGCAAACUAACUUAAGAACAGAAAACCAAGUCCAGCAUCUUCUCACUGAUAAAUGGGAGCUAAACGAAAGAACUUAUGAACACAAAGAAGGAAACAGCAGACACUGGGGUCUAUUUGAGGGGGGGAGGGUGGGAGGAGGGAGAGGAGCAGAAAAGUUAACUAUUGGGUAUGGGCUUAAUACCUGGGUGAUGAAAUAAUAUGUAUAACAAAACCCCAUGACACAUGUUUACCUGUGUAAUGAGCCUUCACAUGCGCCCCCAAACCUAAAAUAAAAAUUAACAAAAAUUUUAUCUACA